GGGGACGCGGAACAGGCGCCUUACCCGCUCCAGGCCUCAGUUUCACCAUUCGUGCAAAGGAGGCUGGUUUCGGUGGAGGAGGAUUUGGGUGGGACUUCGCGGUAAUGCGCCGCGGCGCGGGGGCCUGGGGUCCUCCCCACACCAGGGAAGGGCGAACCGCUCCUGAGCGAGGGGGCUUUUGCGUGGAAUCAGGUGGGUUUGACCUCUGAUUGGGCUAGGUGUCGUGGUGCUAACCUAUGUUAAAGACGCGCAAUCCACCGAAGGGGCAGUGACCUGCUCAAACUCGGCCCCGGGACAAUACGGGGGCCGCUUUCCGCAUUCUAACUGGCUGUGCUGUCUCCCCUCCCCAGGAGCCCGGCGCGACCCCCAGCCGUGCGCCCCGCCCCGGCGCCAUGCAUUGCGAGGUGGCUGAGGCACACUCGGACAAGAGGCCUAAGGAGGCCCCUGGUGCGCCCGGCCCCGACCGCGGCCCCGCCAGCCUCGGCGCGCACAUGGCCUUCAGGGUCACCGUGAGUGGCGGCGGCUGCGGGGACAGGGGCCCGCGGGACCUGCUAGCCCGGCCGCCUGCGCCGCCACCGCGCGCCCACGACCUCCUCCGGCCCCGCAGUCCCCGAGACUACGGUCCAUCCAAGGCCGCCGCCGCCGGGAAGGUGAAUGGGAGCUACGGACACCGUACCCCGGGCUCAGAGAAGAGCCUGCUGGACCUGGACCUUGCUGAGGGCCCUGGCCCCACCUGCUGCCAGGGCCUGUUUCUCCCUGCAGGAAGCCCACCGCCCCGGGCUCACCCCCAAGCUUGUGAGAGGCUGCUGCAUUUCCCCCACCCUGACAGGUCACCUAGACCCCAGGCCACGUAUGUGAACGGCAGCCUCCCAACCACACAACACAUCAAACAGGAGUCCUUGCCCGACUACCAAGCCAUGGCAGAGGCCCGCACAUCCCUGUCUGCCCACUGUCGGGGCCCGCUGGCCACUGGCCUGCACCCAGACCUGGACCUCCCGGGCCGAAGCCUCGCCACCCCUGCGCCUUCCUGCUACCUUCUGGGCAGCGAACCCAGCUCUGGCCUGGGCCUCCAGCCCGAGACCCACCUCCCCGAGGGCAGCCUGAAGCGGUGCUGCGUCUUGGGCCUACCCCCCACCUCCCCAGCCUCCUCCUCACCCUGUGCCUCCUCCGACGUCACCUCCAUCAUCCGCUCCUCCCAGACGUCUCUGGUCACCUGUGUAAAUGGACUCCGGAGCCCCCCUCUGACGGGAGAUCUGGGGGGCCCUUCCAAGCGGGCCCGGCCUGGCCCUGCAUCGACGGACAGCCAUGAGGGCAGCUUGCAACUUGAAGCCUGCCGGAAGGCGAGCUUCCUGAAGCAGGAACCCGCGGAUGAGUUUUCAGAGCUCUUUGGGCCUCACCAGCAGGGCCUGCCGCCCCCCUAUCCCCUGUCUCAGUUGCCGCCUGGCCCAAGCCUUGGAGGCCUGGGGCUGGGCCUGGCAGGCAGGGUGGUGGCCGGGCGGCAGGCGUGCCGCUGGGUGGACUGCUGUGCAGCCUAUGAGCAGCAGGAGGAGCUGGUGCGGCACAUCGAGAAGAGCCACAUCGACCAGCGCAAGGGCGAGGACUUCACCUGCUUCUGGGCUGGCUGCGUGCGCCGCUACAAGCCCUUCAACGCCCGCUACAAGCUGCUCAUCCACAUGCGAGUGCACUCGGGCGAGAAGCCCAACAAGUGCAUGGAGUCCAGGACAACAGAAGGUGCCUCAGCUAGGCCACAAGGCCGACUGCCUGGAUCUUCACAUUUGCUGUUUGCAGAUGUGGAAACUGAGGCCCAUAGAGAGGAUGUGGCUCACUGGAAAUUGCAGAGCGAAAGAGGCAAGCUCAGCAUCCCUCACUCCCAGCCAGUGUCCUGCCUGCUAGACACCACAGUCUGCUGAGUACCACCUGUGUGCUAGUACCACCUGCGGUGAGCACUUACAUGUGUUGCCUUCCAGAUUCUGAAGAACACUGGCUCUUGUCAUGUGCACUGGGAGGAAAUUUCCCAGGUUCAGCAGCUCCUCUGAUGCCCCUCCCAACCCCUGCCACACCCUUUGACAGAUGGGGCCUUGAGACCCAGGGCGGAGAGGUGACCUGCUGGAGGUCACACAGCAGGAGACGGUUGGCGGUGCAUGUAGACCACACGUGUCAAAAUCACCUUCCCUCCUAGCAGGGUCUGAUUCACAAAGAGCUGCUGGGCAGGCUCCAGGGAGACUUUAACCAGUUUCAAAUGUCACACCUUCUUAGUGCAUUGGGAAGGUGUGAUGACUGAUUGCUGUGGGUGUUAGGGUCAGAGGAAGCCUGGCUUGUGCAAAGACCCACACAGGCUUGCACCAGUGCCAGCUCUGCUUCCACUGCCUGGCUCUGCCAGCCUCCUUUCUUCAUUUGCAUGGAGCCACCUGACUGUGGGGCCUUAGUUCCUCUGUAUGUGAUUAGGACUUGGAUUAGAUGAAGUUGGAAGCCCUCCUAGGUCUCCUGACCCUGAUACAGUCUAAGUAGAGACAGUGAGGCCAGGGGUUCAGAGCUAGGUUCCCUCCCCAACUCUGCAUUCAAAUUGUCUGUGGUUCUGGGCAAGUCAUCCCACCCCUCUGAGUCCUCAGUUUUCUCAUCUAUAAAAUGGAAGACUUGGACUCCAUUGAGCUCCAUCCUGUGAGCUCAGACAUUCAGAUGUCCAUAGUUACUUUCCUGCAUUCCUGGCACACCCUAGGGAGGAGGAAGGGGGUGGAGGGCAUGGAAAGGGCAGGUGUGGGCCCCUCCUGAGCUCUCUGGCCCCAGUUCCUUCCACACUCCUCUCUCUUGCUCUGUUCCGGCUGUUCCUCAGAUAUGCUAAGUUCAUUUCCACCUCUGGCUCUUUACAUGGCUGCCCCGUCUGCCUGGAAUGCUCUUGCCCCAGCCUGACCUCUGCUCCCAUGUCACCUCCUCCAGGAGGCCUUCCCUGACUGCCUCUCGAAAGUAGCACCUUUGGCCACUGUCUGCCCCUAUAUUCCACCUGAAAUCCUGUUAUGUGUUUGUCUAUGAUCUGUCCUCCAGCCAAACUUGAGCUCCAUAAAGUCUAGAUGUUUUUGUUUUGUUCCCUCUGUAUCUCCAAUGCCUCAAACAGUUCCCGAUGCACAAUAUGUGAUCAACAGAUAAAUGAAUGUUAGUAAUAAAAAGGGGGAGAGUGGUUCAGUGGGGCAGAAGGAAUGGAACAUGCUAGAAAGGACUCAGACAGAGAGUCAGGACUCUUGUCCUAUGAAGUGGGGGGUUUUGCAGCAGCUCACAGGGUCGUGUUGAGGGCUGCACGGUUGCUGUCCCAGAGGUAUUUCUGGGUCAGCCUAGCUGGGACUGUCCGCCCAGGGAGGCCAGCCCAGUGCCCAGUACCCAGUGGUGCUCAGCACCCACUUACCCCUGACCCCUAUUUCCCUCCCUUCUUCAUCGGCAUUAUCAGGUUACAGGAGAGGCUAUGCCCUCAGUUCACAGCUCCUGGAAUGUCAGAUUCAGACAGGAACAUAGAAACCAUCUGCUGCGACUGGAAACACAAAUUUGGAAACUGAGGCCCAGAGAGGCGUUCUUAUCCAGGUUCCCACACUGUUUCGCUCUUGGAAAGGAAUUUACGAUCAAGUCCUCCACAUAGUAGAUGCUCAGUAAUUAGCUGCUGCUGCAGCAGCUGUUUAUCAUUAAGCCCAUCUCUGCAGAUUCUGUUUUUAUGACCAUGGGCACAGAGGUGGGGCAGGAGUACAAUUUUGCAUUAAUUGAUAACAAAAGGAUGGAAACAGCCAAGAAUGCAGCAGGAAAAAUGAUUCCACCAUCCAAAAACAGCUAUUUUAAAGUGUGAGGAAGGAAGGAAAGCGGCAUUGGUUAGGCACGUGUUCUCUUCCAUAUGCCAGACUAAGGCUUUCGUCCAUGUUUUCUCAGUGGAUCUUGUGAUGCGCUCAUUUUAUGGAUGAGGAAACUGAGGCCCAGAGAGAUCAAGAGCUGGGAUUCCAGCCCCUGGCCUCCCCCUGCUCUGGGGUACCCUCUGUCAGCAUCAGCGAUGACUCCUCUUUUAAAUUGAGCUCACCUUGGAGGACCCCUGACCAGGCCUCUUAAUUAGUUCCUGCGAUUCCUCAAAAGCAGUCACGUGUAAUUUGGGCUCUUCAUGGAUUUGGAGCAUAUCUCUCCACUUAACCUGCACAAAACCUCUGGGGAGGUUUUGCUAAAUCAAGAAUCAGCACUAGGAGCUCAAGGUGUCCUCUUGCCUCACUCCCUGACCUUUGUGUACAGGAAGAUACCAACCUCACAGGUAGGGAGGCCUGUAGGGCUCGGGAAAGGGAGGGCUUGGGGCAGCGGCCUGGGGCUCCAGCCCUGAAAGAGGGUGCAGGAACCAGGUCAGGAUGGAGGGGCUCUGCGGCUCAUGGCUCUACCCAUGGGGGCAGAAGACAGAAUGUGGGGAGGUCCCAUGGCCAGUAAGAGGUGGCAUGGGGUUCAGGUAAGCCUGCAGGCAUAGCCACCCCUCAAGAGGCCUAGGCUCUGCCCCAGGGGCUCCUGGAAUCAAGAUUCUGAUCCCAGGCCUUACCUGAUCCCUUAUUCAUCAGGACGGUGGCUGCACAUGCAUUUUCCUUGUUCUGGUCUCAGUUUACUUACCUGUUCAGUGGAAAUGAUAACCGUGUCCAAUUGCUUACCUGCCCUUUACUCCGUAUAGUCCUACGAUAACCUCAUGUCAUUGGGACCAUUGCCCUAUCUUUCCAACGCAGACACUGGGACUGGAGAGAUAGGGAGCUGGCUGAGCGGCAGGGAGGUCUGUGACAAAGCCCAGGGCAGGCGAUUGCCCUGUGCACCUCUCCCUCUGAGCCCGUUGCCACACCCUGGGGUGUGAUGAUGUUUUCCUGGGCCAGCUCUGCCCCCACGGCUGCCCCCAUGGCUGCCCCCGCGGCAAGCACAGCUUGCGUACUGGGGGAAGACAAGGUGUGGUCCUGAGGAGUGAGGGCUGCUUCCAGCUCCAGCUGAUAGGAACAGAGGGUAUGAUGCCUGCAGUCAGCACCUCUGUCGGGAGGUUGGCAGCUCAUGGCUUCGAAGCACCAGCUCUUUAAUUGUCUCCAUAUUGUGAACCCAGGAAGAUCUGUCCUGACAACUGGUUGGUGAAAUCAGCCAUGGGAUCCCCCUCCCACAGCCUGAGCAGCGGUUUCAGCCUUUCAAAAGCUGUCUGAGGUGGUUACCUAGAGGGUAAAUUAGAUUCACCUGGCAAGGCCUCAUGUCCCCUGGCACGGUCGUGAGAAUGCUGAAGGUUGUUGCCCUUGGAUCUGUGUCAGAGAGAGAAGCAUGGAGUAGGCCUGGGCCCCAGGAAGCUGGGCAGGGGGCAAUAGGAGUGUCCAGUCCCCAUUGGUGAGAUGGUAAAUCCAGUGGGGCUUUCUCAUUGACGUCCUCAAGUUCCAGCACCUCUGCCUUUGGGCCCUUUCCUCCAUGAGAAACAUUUAAAAGUAUAUUUUAUGACAGCAUUGGUAUAAAGAAAAACAUAUUAUGUAUUAACACAUUUUCUUUGACCUAAACUGUUUUUUUUUUUUUUGGAUUUUAAAUUAAAACAUUUUCAUGAGUUCCUAGAAGUAUCAUGGACUGUAGGUUCUGUGCCUGCUGUGUCUCCUAGAAAAUCAGCCCCAAGAGCAAGGCCUGCAGAUCCUGGGGCUGCUUGCAGAAUGGUACAUGUUUUCUUCACCCCUUCCCUUCUCUGGGCUUCAAUUUCAUCCUCUGUGAAAAGGGGUAGGUGGAGGAAAAUCCUGUUGCAAUGUUCUACUCUGCUCCCUUCUGUUACAGUUGAUUUUGUUCCUUAUCAUUGAGUUAUUGUUUUCCAUUAAGAAAUGAUGGAUAGUUACAAUAAAAGAUCUAUGUGCAGUUAAAUUGACAUAGAUUAGAGAAAAGGACAUAAAUACUUGGAAAACCUAAGCUCACUUAAUUAUCGUGAUUGAAUCGUAUAUUUUCCUGGAGCUUCCUGGUAGCCAAAGCAAAGAGGGCAACUUGUUGAUACAGGAUUCUUUUUGAGUGGGAAAGGAAGCAGACCAGCCAGCUUGUGUGCUGGGGGCAGUUUUGUCUGGAUAUUAAUCCCUACGAGGUCUUAUGUGUGAGUCAUAUGAGCUGAUGGCUGGAGGAAGGCUGUAAAAAUGAGAGAGUUCAUUAUUAACAGGUGAUGAUACAGAGACCCUGAACAAAACAAUAGACCUUAUUUUCACAAAUAACUAUGCUACUAUUAUUUGAGAAAAGCCAAGGGCAAGUAAACACUGGUAGUGAAGGACCUAGGUCCUAGUCUGUGUGGUGCUGUUAGCCUAGCAAUAUGUCAGCCCUCUGAGGUAGCUGUCAUUAUCCCCAUUUUACAGUAGAGGACAUUGAGAUUCAGAGAAGUUAAUUAACUUGACCCCGAUCACCCAGUGGGAUUCAGGCUGCUAUAGCAAGCAGCCUGUCUUUGCAGACUUCAAGUCUGAGUCUAUUACUUGAGACUGAUGCAGUCCUUUACUCAAGGAGUCUGUAGCCUAGUGGACUCCAAGGUCCCCGAGGGUGACACUGUUUGCCCUCUUCUUUUACCUGCUUUAAGGAGGUGCUCAGGGGAUGAUGGGGCCUAGGAGAAGGAGCAACAAUCAGCCUGGGCCUAGGGUAGGGGGAUCAGGAUGGCAUCGUGGAGGAGAUAAAAGGGCUUCCAGGAGGAGGCACUGGCAUGGGGAAGGGCCAGGGUGUGAGUUAACGAAGCCUCGCUUGGAGUGGUGGCAGAGGAGGAGAGAAUGUCUACCUGCCAGGUUCCUUAGUUACAAGCAGCAGAAACCAAUCCUGGCCAUAGUGAGCCCUGCAUCCCCACUCAGAAAUAUAUUGGCAGGCUCCAGGGACCACAGGCUAUCUGUCCAAGGGAAGAGGAUCAGACUCAAAACAGGCAGGAUCCCAGGUCCUCCAGGGGCACACAAGCUUAGAGCCUACCCAGACACCAUGAUGGGAUCCUCACUUCUGUGCUCCAGGGCCACAGCUGUAGCAGGGCAACCCACUGGCCAGGCCUGGCUGCCCUCAGGUGGAUAGGGGCUGGACCCUGCUUUGUGGGAGGCAUAGGUGUUCCCUAUUUACAACUUCACUUCCCGCACUCAAGGAGUGAUAGUUCUUACUAUGGGGAAACUGGGCAGCCAGUAAGACUCACGUGUUUGUCAGCUCCAGAAAUGGCUUGAUCUGAGAGAGAGAAUCAGGAGGGACAGGUCACCAGGAGGCAGUGCGGAGUCUGCUAGAUGCAUGGGGUGGGGUGGGGAGCCCAGUUGAGGGCUCCAGCCUCUGGCCUGGGUUCAUUGAGUGGGUGCUGGUGCAGGCCUGGCAGCUUGGGGAGGAAGCUGUGACUUGAUCUGGGGCAUGCUGAAUAGGGAGGUGUCAGCCAGAGGGCCCCAGGGGGGUA